GCCGAAGCUGGCUACUAAGGGAACUUGGGAGGAUCCCACCUCAGCCUUCGUGACUAGUGAGGUGCGCAAACGCCCGAGUUUUCCCUGGUGCGCGGGUUCCGCCUUUGCAGUGCCCUCCACCCUUCCUGGUGUCUGACCCGCCUCCUUCCCAGGCCUUUUGUUCCUGUCCCGGAAAGCCGGCGUCCUGCCGCGCGAUGCCCCUGCUCGGACUUCUUCCCAGGAGGGCCUGGGCUUCGCUGCUCAGCCAGCUCCUGCGACCGCCCUGCGCUUCGUGCACCGGGGCGGUCCGUUGCCAAAGCCAGGGUGAAGAGUCUUUGCAGGUUGCAGAGGCAGUGUUAACAUCCCAACUGAAAGCACAUCAAGAGAAACCAAAUUUUAUUAUCAAGACCCCAAAGGGUACCAGGGAUCUUAGUCCUCAGCAUAUGGUUGUGAGGGAGAAAAUUCUUGAUUUGGUUAUCAGCUGCUUUAAACGUCAUGGAGCAAAGGGGAUGGACACCCCAGCAUUUGAGCUGAAGGAAACCCUGACUGAGAAGUAUGGAGAGGACUCUGGGCUCAUGUAUGAUCUGAAGGAUCAAGGUGGAGAGCUGUUGUCCCUCCGCUAUGACCUUACUGUUCCCUUUGCUCGUUAUCUGGCCAUGAAUAAGGUGAAGAAGAUGAAACGUUAUCAUGUUGGAAAGGUGUGGCGGCGAGAGAGCCCAACCAUAGUCCAAGGCCGUUAUAGGGAGUUCUGCCAGUGUGAUUUUGACAUUGCUGGUCAGUUUGACCCUAUGAUCCCCGAUGCAGAGUGUUUGAAGAUCAUGUGUGAAAUCCUAAGUGGAUUGCAGUUGGGAGACUUUCUCAUUAAGGUAAAUGACCGGCGGAUUGUGGAUGGGAUGUUUGCUGUCUGUGGUGUUCCUGAAAGCAAGUUCCGUGCCAUCUGCUCCUCCAUAGAUAAACUAGACAAGAUGGCUUGGAAAGAUGUGAGACAUGAGAUGGUGGUGAAGAAAGGCCUGGCUCCUGAGGUGGCUGAUCGAAUUGGGGACUAUGUCCAGUGUCAUGGUGGGGUAUCCCUAGUAGAGCAAAUGUUUCAGGAUCCCAGACUAUCCCAGAACAAGCAGGCCCUGGAGGGCCUGGGAGACCUAAAGCUGCUAUUUGAAUACCUGACUUUAUUUGGAAUUGCUGAUAAGAUCUCCUUUGACCUCAGCCUGGCUCGGGGCCUAGACUACUAUACAGGAGUGAUCUAUGAAGCAGUGCUGCUGCAGACCCCAACUCAGGCUGGGGAGGAGCCCCUGAAUGUGGGCAGUGUGGCUGCUGGUGGGCGCUAUGAUGGGCUGGUGGGCAUGUUUGACCCCAAGGGCCACAAGGUGCCAUGUGUGGGACUCAGCAUUGGGGUUGAGCGAAUCUUCUACAUUGUGGAGCAGAGGAUGAAGACCAAAGGUGAGAAGGUGCGGACUACAGAGACUCAAGUGUUUGUGGCCACACCACAGAAGAACUUUCUCCAAGAACGGUUGAAGCUUAUUGCAGAGCUUUGGGAUUCUGGAAUCAAGGCAGAGAUGCUAUACAAGAACAACCCCAAACUAUUAACCCAGCUGCACUAUUGUGAGAGCACAGGCAUUCCACUGGUGGUCAUUAUUGGUGAGCAAGAACUGAAAGAAGGGGUCAUCAAGAUCCGUUCAGUGGCCAGCAGAGAGGAGGUGGCCAUUAAACGGGAAAAUUUUGUGGCUGAAAUUCAGAAGCGACUGUCUGAGUCUUGAUCCUUGCCUGAUUCCCAUCUGCUGCUCUUUGUAGAAAAGGUUUCCUCUAGAACUGAAUUCCUCUGGAAUUGAGUGAUGGACUUCACAACAACUAGCCAGGAAGGGUGACAAGUACCUUCUGCCUCCUCCAUUCUUCCUGGGUGCAGAACUGUAGAAGACCCUGAGGACUCCUGGGCUAGUGUGAGCAGCUAUUCUGCAUGGGUGCAGAUGGCUGGAUGUGAAAGAGACAUGCUCUAGCUGCAGAGGCAAAUUUGAAGUGCCACGGAACGUUGUCAAGAGGUAGUGAGAUUGUUGCUGUGAGCAAGGCUCUGGGAGAGUCACCUCAGGCUCAGGAUUCUGAACCAUUGAGAUCAGAAACCAGAUACUUAGCCUUCUACUGUAGCUACGGAACCAGAUUCUGGUGAAUUUGUCCACAAUCAGCCAUUGGCCUGUCUGGGGAGUUUUUGGAAGACAGCAAAGAGGGGCAAUGGCUGCUUUCAGCUUUGAGGACAGAUGCUAUCCUAAGGGCAUGGCAGUACCCAUGUUGAUUUGACAUCUCUCUAGCCCAUCCAUUGCUUACAGUAGAAGAGUGGGGCUGUAUGCUUGAUAAUCUUGAACAUUGAACUUAAUAGAUGACUUGACAAGGUAGAGAUCUGAUAUUUUGAGAUUUUGGAGACCAUUUCCUGUGCCAGAAUCACUGCUCUAUUCCAUACCGUGCCAUGGAGGCUGUUUUAGAAGUGGUUGGAUAACAUGUUAAAUAAAAUAUUAAGUGUA